GUACAUUCAGGCCACCUGUGCCACCAGCGGGGACGGGCUGUACGAAGGCCUGGACUGGCUGGCCAAUCAGCUCAAAAACAAGAAGUGAAAGCCAGACAGCCCUAACAAAGCACCCCACCCACCCCUGACAUACCUACUGUCACCCUGCCCCAGUCCUACCCCUUCCUCUCCAUGCAAGUGUGGCCAGGGCCCUGGGUAUCAUGUCCACAUGCCCAGCAAGAGCCUUGCCUCCCCUGCCUCCCCUCCUUUUUCCUGUCCACCUAUAUGACCAAUCCCUAAUUGCUGUCCUGAUGAUGAGUCAUUCCAAUUUACUGGAUUUAAAACAAAAAGUUGUUACGGUUUCAUGGGGUGGCCCCUCUCUCUCUCACCCUCUGGGUUUCGGGAGGUCGAGUGGGGUAUUCUCUUUGUUUGGCAGUGGUUGCUGUCCUCUUGGCAUCUGAGUCCUUUCCCUGUCCCCACAAGCCCUUCUACUCCCUGUUUGCCUUUCCUUUGCCACCCUCUCCCUGUUUUACAUGGAAAUUGCACGGGCCUCUCUGUGUUUGCGUGCAUGUGUGCGCCUGUAUAUACAUGUAUAGAGAGAUAUAUUUGUGGGGGCCGGGGGGAGCGGGGAGGGGGUGGAGUGAAGCUCAGGGCUUGCAGCCAGGACACUGCCCACUGGAGCCUGUCAUCUGCCCCUUCCGUGUUGGUGAGAUUAAGGGAAGAAGGUGGGAGGGCAUUAGUCAAGCCGGACUGCCCCAGUCUUUGACUGGUUACCCUCCUCUCUGCAGGUAGGUUUUUCUGGAUGAUAGGACAGAUGAUGGAUUCUUCACCACCAUUUUCCUUGUACUCUUCUCUCCACCCUUCUUAGGGCUGGAGGAUGGCAUUUAUCUCUAGAUGACUGUUCCCAAGGAGAUGCCACUCUGCUCUGCCUUACUGUUGGGAAGGAGAGAGGAACCCACUCACUCUUAUCAGCUUAGAGUGUUCAACUGAUCCUUCCCCACCAUCUUCAGAUCUGUUCCUCUGGAGCUUGACUGGGGGGUGGGGAUGGCAAGUCCAUGGUGUGUGUUAGGGACCCAGGGCAUUGGGGGAAGGGAGGCGAAGGCCUGAGGUUUUCCAUCUUCAUUCUCUUUUGUUAUUAGGAGAAGGUGAGGCAUGGGCCAAUCCCAUUCCUGCCUUCCAGUGCCCCACCACCCUUCUGAUCUUAGGGGUUGGAUGGGUCAUCUGUCCUUGGUCAGAAUUUUCUCACCCUAGUACUCCUACUGGCCUGACCAGGGCUGACUGGGUAUUCUAAUGAGGAGCUGGGAAGUGGGGUGACAUAGCUGACCUUAGUAUCAACCCCCCUCUUCUCCAACUCUUGUUUUCUAGUCCAGGAUAUGCUAAAGGACGAAGAUUUUCUAUUGUUUCCAGGCCCUCAGACCAUCCUUGCUGUCCCUUCACCCUCCAUGCCCCUGCCAUCCUCACUCACUUCUCAUAAAUGGAUCUGGGGGUUAGAGUGGAGGAAAUAAAAUCCUGAAGUGGUUGUCAGUGCUUGUGGGAUGCAGUGGUCUUCAGGAUUCUCCCCGCAUUAUUAUGUAGUUGUUCAGAAGCUGUUGCUACUGCGUCUCUCUGUCUGCAGGGGGCACUUGUUCCUGAGGUCCUCGCCUGGGUCCUGACUUCUGUAGUUUCUGUGAAGACGUGGCUGUCCUGUGGGCUCCUGUGUGUGCUGGCUGCGCCCUGAGCUCCGAGACAGCUGCCCAUAACCUGCUAAGGUCAGGGCCCAGGGCCCCCCACAGCAUGGCUGAGGGACCCCUUCCCAGUAGGGCUGUCCCAAGCCCCACUCCAUGGGGCCAGGUUUCCUGGCCACUUUUGUUGAUAGCAGAUGGAUCAAUAUUAGUAACCCCAUCCAAGAUUGAACUGUGAAAGAGAGGUUCCAGGGGUAUCUCCCUCAGUGCCAGUUACUUAGUGAUGUGUUACCCAGGAUGCAGCAGGUGUGUGCAGGUAUCUUGCUCUCUAGGCCUGUGUGUGUGUGUGAGUGUGUGUGUAUAUGGGUGUGGGUGUGUUUGUGUGUGGUGGUUGUGGGGGGGGUGUUGGAGGUUCUAUUUCAUUUAAAAAUGUAUUCAUUUCCCUGGCCCCACAGAUGCUUCCCUCCAUACUUUUUAUUUGCUCUGUUUCCUCAGAUUUAUUUUGUCUUGCCCCAUUGCCUCUCCUUCCUUGAACUCUUUCCUUUUCAAUCUCAACUCAUUCACUGCUGUUGCUCAUUUGCCCUUUUCCAUGUAUUUUUUCCUACUUAGGAUUUUCCACUCUAUCUUUGUGGUUCAUGAGGACUUUGCCUCUUCUCCUGCCUCAUUCCCUGACUUUCUCUAGUUAGAUGUCAGUCCUAAAUAGGUUUUCCUCACUUCAGGCCUCACCCCUCACCUUGUUUUUUUGGGGGCUCCAGGGACCAAUCUGGGGCUGGAAAUGUUAGGAGGUUGCCUUGGUGCUGCCCCAGAUCUGUCCAGCAGGGGGCAGUAAGUGAUCUUGGUAGUAUCCCUGGCUGCUAAGCCCUUGGCAGGGGUGGUCCUUUCUACAUUCCCAUUCACUUAACAGCUCUUUUGGGAUUGGGUGUUUCAUUCCAUUUCUGCCCACUCCCUCUCCUCUCCUCUCUGGUAGGUUUAAUUUUAUGCUUUCCCUGAUUCCAGCUUUCUGCUUCCUGAGGACUCCCGCUCCCCCCACCCCAAAGUUUGUCUGUGGUGUUAUAGUGGUAACUGCAGUUCCUCCUCUGGAAUGUAGACUGUAUAUGUUUAAUAACUCACCUUCUCUAUCCUUGCUCAAAAUGUGGGAUAACGCGAUGACUGUGACCCUGGUUGGAAAUUAAACUUGUUUUAUGCAGCUUUGGAGCCGACCUUCAUCUUUGCUGUGCAGCAGCCGUGGGACAGUAGUUUCAUGGUGAGGGGAGUCCUGUUUCUGGUCCCUCUCUCCAUAGUGCUCCUUCUUUCAGCAAAGGGGUAAAAGGCACACUUGAUUGAUAGAGAGUAAGGUUAUGGAGGAACUUAGUGCCACUCCACACUGGUUAUUUCUUCCCAUCAUACCCCGCGGCGGGGGAGCCCAAAUGAAUUGGGCAUCAGAGUGUGAGGGCUUCGUGACUUUCCUCCUCUAGUUCUAAAGGGUUUAAACCUGAAAUCAGCUGUAUUUCUCACCUGUUGGUAGACUGUAUGGACUUCACUGGCUGAAGGGCCCUGAACUUGGAGGGCCCCAUGUGCCUCUACUCUCAGAUCUCCUCAGCCUUGCACAUGAGGUGCUUCUAGUUUGAACAGAGACCCCCUCACUAGUCUAGUUCUGGACUUUGGCAGUGAAUAAACAUGAAGGAUAAACGUCUGGGCAGUGUAAUGACCUUAAUCCUUCUUACAACUGAUGGCCCUGCAUCAGCUCUACUUCAGGCGUGUGCUCUUCCGAUCGUAGGUGGAGCCCCCAGAACCAUGUGCCGAGCCCGCUGCUUUUGGAGACACGCUUCACAUACACUACACGGUGAGGGGUCUGGGGGGCCGGGGCGGGGCCUGGGAGGGGGCGGCGCCCUGCUGAAACACGUCAGCUUUGGCUUGGACACGUGGCAAGCGGUUCGGGAGAAGAAACUCGGGGCUCUGGGGUCGUCGAGCACGUGGCGAGGGGAGAGACGUUGCUCUUCCGUGCCUCUUUUCCCUCCUUGCUUUUCUGCCAGUUCCUACCUGGCACGGAGAAGUGCAGGGUGGAGAGAUCUCCGAGAAGCGCCAGCCUUCUGGGGCUUCCUGUUCCUUACAGCGGGAAGCUUGGUAGAUGGACGUAUUAUUGACACCUCCCUGACCAGAGACCCUCUGGUUAUAGAACUUGGCCAAAAGCAGGUGAUUCCAGGUCUGGAGCAGAGUCUUCUCGACAUGUGUGUGGGAGAGAAGCGAAGGGCAAUCAUUCCUUCUCACUUGGCCUAUGGAAAACGGGGAUUUCCACCAUCUGUCCCAGCGGAUGCAGUGGUGCAGUAUGACGUGGAGCUGAUUGCACUAAUCCGAGCCAACUACUGGCUAAAGCUGGUGAAGGGCAUUUUGCCUCUGGUAGGGAUGGCCAUGGUGCCAGCCCUCCUGGGCCUCAUUGGGUAUCACCUAUACAGAAAGGCCAAUAGACCCAAAGUCUCCAAAAAGAAGCUCAAGGAAGAGAAACGAAACAAGAGCAAAAAGAAAUAAUAAAUAAUAAAUUUUAAAAAA